GGGGACUAAGGCGGGGCGUGCAGGUAGCCGGCCGGCCGGGGGUCGCGGGUAUGGCCGAGGCCAGGAAGCGGCGGGAGCUACUUCCCCUGAUCUACCACCAUCUGCUGCGGGCUGGCUAUGUGCGUGCGGCGCGGGAAGUGAAGGAGCAGAGCGGCCAGAAGUGUUUCCUGGCUCAGCCCGUAACCCUUCUGGACAUCUAUACACACUGGCAACAAACCUCAGAGCUUGGUCGGAAGCGGAAGGCAGAGGAAGAUGCGGCACUGCAAGCUAAGAAAACCCGUGUGUCAGACCCCAUCAGCACCUCGGAGAGCUCGGAAGAGGAGGAAGAAGCAGAAGCCGAAACCGCCAAAGCCACCCCAAGACUAGCAUCUACCAACUCCUCAGUCCUGGGGGCGGACUUGCCAUCAAGCAUGAAAGAAAAAGCCAAGGCAGAGACAGAGAAAGCUGGCAAGACUGGGAAUUCCAUGCCACACCCUGCCACUGGGAAGACGGUGGCCAACCUUCUUUCUGGGAAGUCUCCCAGGAAGUCAGCAGAGCCCUCAGCAAAUACUACGUUGGUCUCAGAAACUGAGGAGGAGGGCAGCGUCCCGGCCUUUGGAGCUGCUGCCAAGCCUGGGAUGGUGUCAGCGGGCCAGGCCGACAGCUCCAGCGAGGACACCUCCAGCUCCAGUGAUGAGACAGACGUGGAGGGGAAACCCUCAGUAAAACCAGCCCAGGUCAAAGCCUCAUCAGUUUCUACUAAGGAGUCUCCAGCAAGAAAGGCGGCCCCAGCCCCUGGGAAGGUGGGGGAUGUGACACCCCAGGUCAAAGGAGGGGCCCUGCCCCCAGCCAAGAGGGCCAAGAAGCCAGAAGAGGAGUCAGAGAGUAGUGAGGAGGGAUCUGAAAGUGAGGAGGAGGCCCCUGCAGGGACACGAAGCCAGGUAAAGGCCUCUGAAAAAAUUCUCCAGGUCAGAGCUGCCUCAGCCCCUGCCAAGGGGACCCCUGGGAAAGGGGCUACCCCAGCACCCCCUGGGAAGGCAGGGGCUGUAGCCUCCCAGACCAAGGCAGGGAAGCCAGAGGAGGACUCAGAGAGCAGCAGCGAGGAGUCAUCUGACAGUGAGGAGGAGACGCCAGCUGCCAAGGCCCUGCUUCAGGCGAAGGCCUCAGGAAAAACCUCUCAGGUCGGAGCUGCCUCAGCCCCUGCCAAGGAGUCCCCCAGGAAAGGAGCUGCCCCAGCGCCCCCUGGGAAGACAGGGCCUGCAGUUGCCAAGGCCCAGGCGGGGAAGCGGGAGGAGGACUCGCAGAGCAGCAGCGAGGAAUCGGACAGUGAGGAGGAGGCGCCUGCUCAGGCGAAGCCUUCAGGGAAGGCCCCCCAGGUCAGAGCCGCCUCGGCCCCUGCCAAGGAGUCCCCCAGGAAAGGGGCUGCCCCAGCACCUCCUAGGAAAACAGGGCCUGCAGCCGCCCAGGUCCAGGUGGGGAAGCAGGAGGAGGACUCAAGAAGCAGCAGCGAGGAGUCAGACAGUGACAGAGAGGCACUGGCAGCCAUGAAUGCAGCUCAGGUGAAGCCCUUGGGGAAAAGCCCCCAGGUGAAACCUGCCUCUACCAUGGGCAUGGGGCCCUUGGGGAAAGGCGCCGGCCCAGUGCCACCCGGGAAGGUGGGGCCUGCAACCCCCUCAGCCCAGGUGGGGAAGUGGGAGGAGGACUCAGAGAGCAGUAGUGAGGAGUCAUCAGACAGCAGUGAUGGAGAGGUGCCCACAGCUGUGGCCCCGGCUCAGGAAAAGUCCUUGGGGAACAUCCUCCAGGCCAAACCCACCUCCAGUCCUGCCAAGGGGCCCCCUCAGAAGGCAGGGCCUGUAGCCGUCCAGGUCAAGGCUGAAAAGCCCAUGGACAACUCGGAGAGCAGCGAGGAGUCAUCGGACAGUGCGGACAGUGAGGAGGCACCAGCAGCCAUGACUGCAGCUCAGGCAAAACCAGCUCUGAAAAUUCCUCAGACCAAGGCCUGCCCAAAGAAAACCAAUACCACUGCAUCUGCCAAGGUCGCCCCUGUGCGAGUGGGCACCCAAGCCCCCCGGAAAGCAGGAACUGCGACUUCUCCAGCAGGCUCAUCCCCAGCUGUGGCUGGGGGCACCCAGAGACCAGCAGAGGAUUCUUCAAGCAGUGAGGAAUCAGAUAGUGAGGAAGAGAAGACAGGUCUUGCAGUAACCGUGGGACAGGCAAAGUCUGUGGGGAAAGGCCUCCAGGUGAAAGCAGCCUCAGUGCCUGUCAAGGGGUCCUUGGGGCAAGGGACUGCUCCAGUACUCCCUGGGAAGACGGGGCCUACAGUCACCCAGGUGAAAGCUGAAAAGCAGGAAGACUCUGAGAGCAGUGAGGAGGAAUCAGACAGUGAGGAAGCAGCUGCAUCUCCAGCACAGGUGAAAACCUCAGUAAAGAAAACCCAGGCCAAAGCCAACCCAGCUGCCGCCAGAGCACCUUCAGCAAAAGGGACAAUUUCAGCCCCUGGAAAAGUUGUCACUGCAGCUGCUCAAGCCAAGCAGAGGUCUCCAUCCAAGGUGAAGCCACCAGUGAGAAACCCCCAGAACAGUACCGUCUUGGCGAGGGGCCCAGCAUCUGUGCCAUCUGUGGGGAAGGCCGUGGCUACAGCAGCUCAGGCCCAGACAGGGCCAGAGGAGGACUCAGGGAGCAGUGAGGAGGAGUCAGACAGUGAGGAGGAGGCGGAGACGCUGGCUCAGGUGAAGCCUUCAGGGAAGACCCACCAGAUCAGAGCUGCCUUGGCUCCUGCCAAGGAGUCCCCCAGGAAAGGGGCUGCCCCAACACCUCCUGGGAAGACAGGGCCUUCGGCUGCCCAGGCAGGGAAGCAGGAUGACUCAGGGAGCAGCAGCGAGGAAUCAGACAGUGAUGGGGAGGCACCGGCAGCUGUGACCUCUGCCCAGAAGGACAGUAACUCCAAACCUGCCAGAAGCAAGACCCUGGCCCCAGCACCCCCAGAGAGGAACACGGAGGGGUCCUCGGAGAGCAGUGAGGAAGAGCUGCCACUGACCCAGGUGAUUAAACCCCCUCUGAUUUUUGUCGACCCUAAUCGUAGUCCAGCUGGCCCAGCUGCUACACCCGCACAAGCCCAGGCUGCAAGCACCCCGAGGAAGGCCCGAGCCUCGGAGAGCACAGCCAGGAGCUCCUCCUCCGAGAGCGAGGAUGAGGACGUGAUCCCCGCUACACAGUGCUUGACUCCUGGCAUCAGAACCAAUGUGGUGACCAUGCCCACUGCCCACCCAAGAAUAGCCCCCAAAGCCAGCAUGGCUGGGGCCAGCAGCAGCAAGGAGUCCAGUCGGAUAUCAGAUGGCAAGAAACAGGAGGGACCAGCCACUCAGGUGUCAAAGAAGAACCCAGCUUCCCUCCCACUGACCCAGGCUGCCCUGAAGGUCCUCGCCCAGAAAGCCAGUGAGGCUCAGCCUCCUGUUGCCAGGACCCAGCCUUCAAGUGGGGUUGACAGUGCUGUGGGAACACUCCCUGCAACAAGUCCCCAGAGCACCUCCGUCCAGGCCAAAGGGACCAACAAGCUCAGAAAACCUAAGCUUCCUGAGGUCCAGCAGGCCACCAAAGCCCCUGAGAGCUCAGAUGACAGUGAGGACAGCAGCGACAGUUCUUCAGGGAGUGAGGAAGAUGGUGAAGGGCCCCAGGGGGCCAAGUCAGCCCACACGCUGGUAGGUCCCACCCCCUCCAGGACAGAGACCCUGGUGGAGGAGACCGCAGCAGAGUCCAGCGAGGAUGAUGUGGUGGCGCCAUCCCAGUCUCUCCUCUCAGGUUAUAUGACCCCUGGACUAACCCCAGCCAAUUCCCAGGCCUCAAAAGCCACUCCCAAGCUAGACUCCAGCCCCUCAGUUUCCUCUACUCUGGCCGCCAAAGAUGACCCAGAUGGCAAGCAGGAGGCAAAGCCCCAACAGGCAGCAGGCAUGUUGUCCCCUAAAACAGGUGGAAAAGAGGCUGCUUCAGGCACCACACCUCAGAAGUCCCGGAAGCCCAAGAAAGGGGCUGGGAACCCCCAAGCCUCAACCCUGGCGCUGCAAAGCAACAUCACCCAGUGCCUCCUGGGCCAACCCUGGCCCCUGAAUGAGGCCCAGGUGCAGGCCUCAGUGGUGAAGGUCCUGACUGAGCUGCUGGAACAGGAAAGAAAGAAGGUGGUGGACACCACCAAGGAGAGCAGCAGGAAGGGCUGGGAGAGCCGCAAGCGGAAGCUAUCGGGAGACCAGCCAGCUGCCAGGACCCCCAGGAGCAAGAAGAAGAAGAAGCUGGGGGCCGGGGAAGGUGGGGAGGCCUCUGUUUCCCCAGAAAAGACCUCCACGACUUCCAAGGGGAAAGCAAAGAGAGACAAAGCAAGUGGUGAUGUCAAGGAGAAGAAAGGGAAGGGGUCUCUUGGCUCCCAAGGGGCCAAGGACGAGCCAGAAGAGGAGCUUCAGAAGGGGAUGGGGACGGUUGAAGGUGGAGAUCAAAGCAACCCAAAGAGCAAGAAGGAGAAGAAGAAAUCCGACAAGAGAAAAAAAGACAAAGAAAAAAAAGAAAAGAAGAAGAAAGCAAAAAAGGCCUCAACCAAAGAUUCUGAGUCACCGUCCCAGAAGAAAAAGAAGAAAAAGAAGAAGACAGCAGAGCAGACUGUAUGACGAGCACCAGCACCAGGCACAGGGAUUUCCUAGCCGAGCAGUGGCCAUCCCCAUGCCUCUGACCUCCACCGACCUCUGCCCACCAUGGGUUGGAACUAAACUGUUACCUUCCCUCGCUCCACAGAAGAAGACAGCCAGCUUCAGGGGUCCCUGUGCUGGCCAAGCCAGUGAGCCUGCGGGGAGGCUGGUCCAAGGAGAAAGUGGACCAGCUCCCAUGACCUCACCCCACUCCCCCAACACAGGACGCUUCAUAUAGAUGUGUACAGUAUAUGUAUUUUUUUAAGUGACCUCCUCUCCUUCCACAGACCCCACAUGCCCAAAGGCCUCGGGACUUCCCACCACCUUGCUCCACAGAUCCAGCUAGGCCUGACCUGUGCCUCAUCCCGUGCCGCUCGGUCUCUGGCUGAUCCCGAGGCUUUGUCUUCCUCUCGUCAGUUCUUUUGGUUGUGUUUUUUGUUUUUUUUUUAAUAACUCAAAAAAAAAAUAAAAGACUUGGAGGAAGGGUG